AGGAUUUGGAAGGAGUGCCACCCUCUAAAAAGAUGAAACUGGAGGCCUCUCAACAAAACUCCGAAGAGAUGUAGACGAUGCUUUAAAGCCUCCGAUCCAUGUUCCAUGGAAGGUACAUCAGCAAUUAAUUCUAGAGCAACUUUGCCCCAGCGAUUCCUCUUGGGUGCGAACAGAACUACUAACGUUUCAAGUUUACCAAGUGCAAAUCCAAGAAGACCCAGAACGGCGUCACUUCUCAGACACUGAAGAACUCUGCUGUGAAGCAAAACACUCAAACCUUUAAGGGACUGUCCUUGGGGAGGCAGGCGGGGCUGACAGCUCAGGAGUGUCUGCACACUGUCUCGGAAGCCAGGAUUCCAUUUGUGUUGCUGCUGUAUUUUCCCCCCACUUCUCUAUGUAACGAUAUAAGCUAUCGGAGGGUGGUACCGAUCAGGAACGCUUUUUGGCGGGGCUUUCCACUGUUCAACCGAUUCCUUCCGCUUUCUUUUUUUGUGCCUUGUGCCCUUGAGGUGACCUCUGGCAUGUAUCCUGGUGGUUCUUACAUCCCCCUCUGCAAAGUGCCCUCUUGGUUUGGUUCGGGCGGCGGCUGCCACCCUACUCACCGCUCUCCUCCCUGCCCCAGGACUUCAUCGGAGCAGGCAGGGUGGAGCGAAGGAGCUCCUUAGCCCACCUGGUUUGCAGGUGCAGGGGGACCUUAGGCACGCCCCAAGCACCAGGCACCAGGGCCCAAGGACGCGCAGGUGUUGGGGCACAGUCCCCAAGGGCUCGGCCCCUUGGAUCAGGCUGGGCACUCGCUGUGCUCUCCCCUCCUUGGGGCGUUUAGGACUGGGCGUCUCCAAGCCCACCAUGGCCCAGAUGGACGUGCAAAGCCCUUGGAAUUUUCUGGCACUUCCUCUCUAUUGCCCCCACCACCACCACCCCCAUCACUGCUUUCUCCCAGACCUCCGAAUACGAAAUGGCUUCUCUGGCUGACUGCAAGGCUGUCUCCUUAAGGCACUGAGUGGGCCGGGGAGGCUGGGAGCCGGCGGCAGGAUUAGCUGGUGCUGAACUUUCUCUCAUAGGACGUCGCUUGGAUUUCAAAUCCACGGUCACCUGCUGCCCUUUGCCUCCCCCGACGCCCCAGCCUGUGCCCCGGAGAGGCAGGAUCGCAGUGGUCAGAAUCCACGUGCUUUCCUAUUCUCAGGCUGUUCUGACUCUGAGCCAACAGCUGGACCGUGUCUCAUCCCCAGAACAUGCCGUCUGUCCCCACCGGGGAGUGGGCCUUGAUGGCCGGGCCUCGAAGGCCACAAACAAGGCGUCGAGGAAUUGGAAAGAUUUGCACACCCUCCAGAAAGGAGAGACGCAAUCUCCCCUCCCUCCCAUCCCCCACCUUCGCUGGAACAGCUUCCUCUCACUGAACGGAGACGCCCCCUUGGACGAACUGCCUAAUCGUUUGGUUCUGAGGCCUGGUUUGCUCUUAAUUAAUAUAUGAACUCCUCAGACCUUAAACCUUUUCCUAAGCUUUCUUUACUGCACUGGAGUUCUGACUCCCUUUGAGUUGUGUGUUACUGGGGGUGGGGUGGGGUCAUGGGUUUUGUUGUUUUUGGGGGCUAAUUGGUGCAUAUUCAGGUACCACCUUUGACGUGUGGCUCUUUCUCCUGACCAUCAUGGGAAGUGUCUGCUGGAUUCCAUUUUCUAAGAGUUUCUGAGGGUGAGGCUCUUAUUUUUUUUUUUAAGGGAUCCUGUCUAUUUCCUGCACUUCGAGAAGAAUCAAAAUGUUCCUGAAUUUCAAAUACCUCAUGCAAAAUGUCUCCUGAAAUAAGGGAAAAAAAAAAAACCACAACUUUGAAAAUCUUAAUGUUGAAGUUAGCAAUGCCGAAAGGUUUCUGUCUUAAAAAAAAAAAUCCUUGUACUUAUCAAUUUUGCCCCUUAGGCAGUCAGUUUUGUUGAGAACUGUGUCCUGCAUCCUGGCGCAGAACCUACCUGAUGCGGUUCCUCUCCACGCAUCUCGAGGCGGCGUUACCUCCAGAUUCCGUAGAGUUAGAGUCACAUUUUUCUUUGCAGCGAAACUCCAUCUUGGUGAGAGAUGAAUUUGGAUAUUUAUUUCCUUCUCUGUUUUUGGGAAACGAGAGGCUACAACCAAGACAGCUGAAGGAGAAUGAAACACACACAUCCACAGAAACAGAGAGGCGUAGGUGGCCCUGCCGUUGACCGCAGCCUCUCUGGACAGGCAAGGGGAGUUGGCGCAGGUGAGGACUCAGACGACGUCCACCGUCCCAAGGCUGUCACUAGUAUUUCUCUGAAGUGCCUGAAGGUAGGAAUGGGCCGGCGAUUGGGACCAGCUGGGCCCCACCACGGCCACGCCAGGCAAAGCGCCAGCAGCCCUGCACUCCACGCUGGCCAAGAAGGCCUUCCACGCAGAAUGACAAGACUGCAAAAAUCCGAUGUGCUUCCUUCCCUGGCGCAGUCGCUCCUCGAGCCGCUGCCCCCCACCCACCCUGCACCCCUCGCCCUCCCCCCACCACAGAAUCUAAGACCUUUCAGCUUCGAGCCAGGGGGCGGGGGAUCCCGAGCAAAAGCCUUCCGUGGACAUCAGGCCCCGUGGCCUCAAGGGCUCCCAGGGCAAACCUAAUUCCCCCCAAAACGUGAAGUCGGGGAAGCUGCGGCUACACAUUCCACAAAGUGCUGGCACUUACACCCACAACCCGGAAGGCUGUGGACCGAUUCCUCUAGGGUGGUGACCUCCCAUUAGCAAACGGUGUCAUGGUUUGGAAUGUUCAUUAUCGCCAAGAACCUGGUUAGAGGCAUAAAGACCUUUUUUCACCGUUACCUAAUUUUUUCCCCUUUCAAGAAUUUUUUUUUUUUUUGGUGUGUUGUACAGCAGUAUAAUUUUUCACUUAUUUAUUCCAUCAGUAGAUAUGGUUUGUACAAUGUACAAUUGUUUCAUUUCAGAAAAUAAAAAUUUCAAAUCAUGAA